CCCCUUUGGAGCUACUUCCUCAUGCUGCCCGCUCGCCUACCGUUCAGGCUGCUGAGCCUUUUCCUUCGUGGAUCCGCUCCCACGGCAGCGCGCCAUGGCCUCCGGGAGCCGCUCCUGGAGAGGAGGUGCGCUGCCGCCUCCUCCUUCCAGCACUCAUCGAGUCUGGGACGCGAGCUUCCUUAUGACCCCGUGGACACGGAGGGCUUUGGAGAAGGUGGUGACAUGCAGGAGCGUUUUCUGUUCCCGGAGUACAUCCUGGAUCCGGAGCCGCAACCCACCCGCGAAAAGCAGCUGCAGGAGCUCCAGCAACAGCAGGAGGAGGAGGAGCGACAGAGGCAGCAGCGGCGGGAGGAGCGGCGACAGCAAAACCUACGGGCCAGGUCCCGGGAGCACCCGGUCGUGGGGCACCCGGACCCGGCAUUGCCGCCCAGCGGCGUGAACUGCUCGGGCUGUGGGGCAGAGCUGCACUGCCAGGACGCCGGAGUGCCCGGCUACCUGCCCCGAGAGAAGUUCCUCCGCACGGCGGAGGCAGACGGCGGGCUGGCACGGACCGUGUGCCAGCGCUGCUGGCUGCUGUCGCACCACCGGCGCGCUCUACGCCUGCAGGUGAGCCGCGAGCAGUACCUGGAGCUGGUGAGCGCCGCGUUGCGGCGGCCCGGCCCCUCCCUGGUGCUCUACAUGGUGGACCUGCUGGACCUGCCCGACGCCCUGCUGCCCGACUUGCCCGCGCUGGUGGGCCCCAAGCAGCUGAUCGUGCUGGGAAACAAAGUGGACCUCCUGCCCCAGGAUGCUCCUGGCUACCGGCAGAGGCUGCGGGAGCGACUGUGGGAGGACUGUGCCCGCGCCGGGCUCCUGCUGGCCCCUGGCCACCAAGGGCCACAGCGCCCCGUCAAGGACGAGCCACAGGACGGGGAGAAUCCGAAUCCGCCGAACUGGUCCCGCACAGUGGUCAGGGACGUGCGGCUGAUCAGCGCCAAGACCGGCUAUGGAGUGGAAGAGUUGAUCUCUGCCCUUCAGCGCUCCUGGCGCUACCGUGGGGACGUCUACUUAGUGGGCGCCACCAACGCCGGCAAAUCCACUCUCUUUAACACGCUCCUGGAGUCCGAUUACUGCACUGCCAAGGGCUCCGAGGCCAUCGACAGAGCCACCAUCUCCCCUUGGCCAGGUACUACAUUAAACCUUCUGAAGUUUCCUAUUUGCAACCCAACUCCUUACAGAAUGUUUAAAAGGCAUCAAAGACUUAAAAAAGAUUCAACUCAAGCUGAAGAAGAUCUUAGUGAGCAAGAACAAAAUCAGCUUAAUGUCCUCAAAAAGCAUGGUUAUGUCGUAGGAAGAGUUGGAAGGACAUUCUUGUAUUCAGAAGAACAGAAGGAUAACAUUCCCUUUGAGUUUGAUGCUGAUUCACUUGCCUUUGACAUGGAAAAUGACCCUGUUAUGGGUACACACAAAUCCACCAAACAAGUAGAAUUGACUGCACAAGAUGUGAAAGAUGCCCACUGGUUUUAUGACACCCCUGGAAUUACAAAAGAAAAUUGUAUUUUAAAUCUUCUAACAGAAAAAGAAGUAAAUAUUGUUUUGCCAACACAGUCCAUUGUUCCAAGAACUUUUGUGCUUAAACCAGGAAUGGUUCUGUUUUUGGGUGCUAUAGGCCGCAUAGAUUUCCUGCAGGGAAAUCAGUCAGCUUGGUUUACAGUCGUGGCUUCCAACAUCCUCCCUGUGCAUAUCACCUCCUUGGACAGGGCAGACGCUCUGUAUCAGAAGCAUGCAGGUCAUACGUUACUCCAGAUUCCAAUGGGUGGAAAAGAACGAAUGGCAGGAUUUCCUCCUCUUGUUGCUGAAGACAUUAUGUUAAAAGAAGGACUGGGGGCAUCUGAAGCAGUGGCCGACAUCAAGUUUUCCUCUGCAGGUUGGGUUUCAGUAACACCUAAUUUUAAGGACAGACUGCAUCUCCGAGGCUAUACACCUGAAGGAACAGUUUUGACCGUCCGGCCCCCUCUCUUGCCAUAUAUUGUUAACAUCAAAGGACAGCGCAUCAAGAAAAGUGUGGCCUAUAAAACCAAGAAGCCUCCUUCCCUUAUGUACAACGUGAGGAAGAAGAAAGGAAAGAUAAAUGUAUGAGACCGACCUUGUUCACUCCAGAUAUUAACUGUAUUGAACACAACAAAAUACAUUGAAUUUGUAUUAAACAUAUAACGCAUAAAUAAAGCUCCCAUUCUUA